GCGGAUGCGGAUGCGGAUGCGAAGGUGGCGGCCGAGGUGGCGGCCGAGGUGGCGGCUGCGGCGGCCGCCGCGGAUGCAGAUGCGGAUGAGACCCUCGGUGACUGUGAGGGGAACCCAGAUUUUCAGAUGGCCUCCCUGUACGUGGGCGACCUGCACCCUGAGGUGACCGAGGCAAUGCUGUACGAGAAGUUCAGUCCAGCUGGGCCCAUCCUCUCCAUCCGCAUCUGCAGGGACAAGAUCACCCGCCGCUCAUUGGGCUACGCGUAUGUCAACUACCAGCAACCGGUGGACGCCAAGCGGGCCCUGGAGACCCUGAACUUUGAUGUCAUAAAGGGCAGGCCAGUGCGCAUCAUGUGGUCCCAGAGGGACCCGUCGCUCCGCAAGAGCGGGGUGGGCAACGUCUUCAUCAAGAACCUGGGCAAGACCAUCGACAACAAGGCGCUGUACAACAUCUUCUCGGCGUUCGGCAACAUCCUCUCCUGCAAAGUGGCCUGUGACGAAAAGGGGCCCAAGGGCUACGGGUUCGUGCACUUCCAAAAGCAGGAAUCUGCGGAGCGGGCCAUCGAUGUGAUGAAUGGCAUGUUCCUGAACUACCGCAAAAUUUUCGUCGGGAGAUUCAAGUCGCAUAAAGAACGAGAGGCCGAAAGGGGAGCCUGGGCCAGGCAGUCCACUAGUGCUGACGUCAAGGAUUUCGAGGAAGACACCGACGAGGAGGCCACCUUGCGAUGAAGACAUCCCAGGAGCUAGCCAGCCAGCAGAGCCAAACCUUGGCUCACACCCGGUUUACAACCCCCCACCCCCAGCCCUCCCCCGCCAACCCACCAGCAGUGUAUUUAUUGUAUUGAGAGUGCAGGUCUCUCUCUCUCUCUCUCUCCCCUUCUCUCUCCCCGCUUCCUAUUUUCUCCCUCCACCUCUCCUCUCCUUCCCUUCCUCUCCCCCGCCCACCCCCACCAAGGGCGUUGUGAAUAAUCUUACUAAUCUGUGCCAUUUGUAGGUUAAAGGCUGCCUCUUCUCCCUGUGGUUUGAUUUAAAAAGCAUUUUCAUUCUCUCUUUGUUUACUGCACAGGUGGUACAAUUUCAUGGUAGAAUCAUCAGAAAGGAGAAGGAUAUCAGAUGAGGGAAGAAACAAGAGAGUAAUUGCUCCCCUGGUCCUACUCCCCAGAGAGAACCACUUUUACCUUUUUGGUGUGCUGCUUUUCCAGGCUCUCUUCUCUCCCUCUCUCUCCUUUGCUCACCCCCACCCCGCCUUCCCUUUUAACACACCGUUAUAGAAUGGUUCAUGUAUGUGGUGUUUCUUAACCUGCUUUUUCAGCAACUAAAACCAAACAAAAAUCAACCCAUUGAACUUCUUUCCAUGUUAUCAACAGGCUUAUGAAACGUCAUCUUCAGUGCCUGCAGAGUGCUCCAGUGUAUCCGUGGACCUUAACAUUUCUGUAAUCAUUCCCGCAUUGUUGGACAUUCAGGUGGUGCCUAGUUCUUUCCCUGUGUUUAAGACCAACAUUGCGUGCUCUGUGCUUUGAUGAGUGAAUCCUUCCUUGUCAAGCCAAAUCUUUGCUAGCAUCCCGGUGGUCUCCUUAACUGCGGACUUGCAAGAUCCACAUAUAGACAUUUUAAAGACUUUUCCUGUGUGUUGCCAAAAGGCCCCCUUCAUAAGCAUUGUACCGAUUUGCACUCGUGCCGGCCAGCGCAGCUAGUAAAGAGUAUGCCCGUUUCCCCUGCAUAGUCUCCUGGUCACUGUAAUUGAUCGUGUGUGUGCGUGCGUGUGUGUGUGUGUGUGUGUGUGUGUGUGUCUUGGCCAGCUUGGCGGGCUACAAAGGGUGUUUCGCUGUCCUCGGUAGUUUUGCUGGAAACAAACACUGCUUAUGACCCCAUUCCCCUGUGCCCUCUUCCUGUCCUUUUCCCUGUUGUCAGAAAAGUAAUUCAGCGUCAUUGCAAGAAAAAAAAAUCACAAAGCAGACAAGUUACCAGAAGAAAAUUAAAGUCACCAGUAAUCAUUUCUGAUGAUUACACACACAUUCCAGAAACAUUUUCAUGCACACCUCUCUGAUAUUUUCUAGAACUACCUGAAACAUUUUUGUCUGUAGGUCUAGUUUUUUUCUUAUGCAUAUAUCAUAUAUGUAUAUUAUGAUGUACAGACUGUUUUUAUAUCUGCUUUUCACACAUACAUGUGUGUGUAUAUUUAUACACACACAUAUUCUUGAACUUCAUUUCAUGUCAUUAAAGAUACUUUUAAAAUA